GCGCCUGACCGCGGCAGCUCCCACCAUGGCGGAGACCAAGCUCCAGCUGUUUGUCAAGGCGAGUGAGGACGGGGAGAGCGUGGGUCACUGCCCCUCCUGCCAGCGGCUCUUCAUGGUCCUGCUCCUCAAGGGCGUACCUUUCACCCUCACCACGGUGGACACGCGCAGGUCCCCGGACGUGCUGAAGGACUUCGCCCCCGGCUCGCAGCUGCCCAUCCUGCUCUAUGACAGCGACGCCAAGACAGACACGCUGCAGAUCGAGGACUUUCUGGAGGAGACGCUGGGGCCGCCCGACUUCCCCAGCCUGGCGCCUCGUUACAGGGAGUCCAACACCGCCGGCAACGACGUUUUCCACAAGUUCUCCGCGUUCAUCAAGAACCCGGUGCCCGCGCAGGACGAAGCCCUGUACCAGCAGCUGCUGCGCGCCCUCGCCAGGCUGGACAGCUACCUGCGCGCGCCCCUGGAGCACGAGCUGGCGGGGGAGCCGCAGCUGCGCGAGUCCCGCCGCCGCUUCCUGGACGGCGACAGGCUCACGCUGGCCGACUGCAGCCUCCUGCCCAAGCUGCACAUCGUCGACACGGUGUGCGCGCACUUCCGCCAGGCGCCCAUCCCCGCGGAGCUGCGCGGCGUACGCCGCUACCUGGACAGCGCGAUGCAGGAGAAAGAGUUCAAAUACACGUGUCCGCACAGCGCCGAGAUCCUGGCGGCCUACCGGCCCGCCGUGCACCCCCGCUAGCGCCCCACCCCGCGUCUGUCGCCCAAUAAAGGCAUCUUUGUCGGGAGUGAGGGUGUCCUGACAUCUGAAGGGC